GCCACCCACCACCAUGGACCCCCGUCUGCCCGCCUGGGCGCUGGUGCUGCUGGGCCCUGCCCUGGUGUUCGCGUUGGGCCCCGCGCCCACCCCAGAGAUGCGUGAGAAGUUGUGCGGCCACCACUUCGUACGCGCGCUAGUGCGCGUGUGCGGGGGCCCCCGCUGGUCCACCGAAGCCAGGAGGCCUGCGACCGGAGGCGACCAGAGGGAGUCUCACUCUGUUUCCCAGGCUGGUCUCAAACUCCUGAGCUCAAGUAAUCCUCCCACCUUGACCUUCCAAAGUGUUGGGAUUAGCGAUGUGAGUUGCUACAGUGGCUGGAGAGACGACAUCUGCUCCAUGGGCUGGUGGCCGACAGUAAUCUCACGCUGGGACCUGGCCUGCAGCCCCUGCCCCAGACCUCUCACCAUCACCGCCACCACCGUGCAGCUGCCACCAACCCUGCACGCUACUGCUGCCUCAGUGGCUGUACCCAACAAGACCUGCUGACCCUCUGUCCCUACUGAUUCCUCCUUGGGUGCAGCCUCAGAGUGGCCUGAGGCCCAGAGGGUCUGGUCUGGUGAGCUCCUGAGGCCACACAGCACCAUAAAGUCUCGCAUCUACAGGCCUUUGAUUACCUCCUGGGAUGGGUGCUCACUAUCUACCCCAGACCAAUGCCACCUGCAGCCUGUGGAGUCAACUGCAGAAUAAAUCACACCCUAGCCCUGGCUUGGAGGAUCCCCGCUUUCACAGAUGCUGGACACUGACAGCCAAAUGUCCUCACUCCAGGGGAGCCCCAGACGCUCCGCUCCCUGCAUGUGUAACACCCCUUCUUGCUGUCUCUUAGUAAAUAAACGACCCAAAGCAGC